CUGGCGCGGCGUUUUCCUCUGGCUCCUGCGAGGGCUUGGUUUAGGGCUUCGGCUCUCUGCGUUCUCGGCUCCGGGAGGCCUCGGUGAUUCAGCCACAGCCUCUGCCUCCCGUUGCUCUGUGACCUGAGGGUAUUGGACAAUUUGUAGCUAAGACUCCCGGAUACCCUGAAGUCGGGAAAUGGUGAGUGUGCGGGGCAGGGCGUCCGGAGGCUGGGGAGGCCUCAUCGGAACCGGCGGGAAAUGGCGGCGGCGGGACCGAGUCUGCGAACGGAGUCCCCGCUGCCGCCUCUCAGCCCUCAGUCCCCUCCGGUGACGGACCGGGCUCCUGUCGGUCCCCGCACGGCGGCUCUGGCCCAGCCUGCGGCCCUCCUUGUGCAGUUCUGCGCCCGCAGCCCCGCACCUUCCCUGGGCCGUGGGGUGAGGAGGAGCUCAUCUGGAAGACGCCGGCGCCCGCGUGCGAGGUGCCCGCCUGGGAGGAGCUGUGGUCCGGGGGUCCGGUCCCUACUUUACCCUGUUCGGAAUGAGAUCGAGGCCCCAUCGAAACAAAGUUCAUGUGAGCAAACGGGGUCUCAUUAAUGGGACAGCGUCGGCCGCGGCUCCUGGUUUGGGGACUGCCAGCGGGUCUUGAAGGAAAGGCUUUUGUGAGGUGUGUGAGCAAGCGAAGCAAAUCACCCGCCCGCUCCAACUAUUCCACCAGUCCCUUUGCCCUGUGCACCUCCUCCGCGUGGCUGUUCCUGAGUAACAUCUUUUAGAAUACGCUGGUGUCGGUGCGCACGGCGCUUCUCAGUUCUGAACUCGUAACAUUCAGGGAUGUGGCCAUAGAAUUCUCCCCUGAAGAGUGGAAAUGUCUGGACCCUGCCCAGCAGAAUUUGUAUAGAGAUGUGAUGUUGGAGAACUACAGGAACCUGGUCUCCCUGGGUUUUGUGAUCUCUAACCCAGACCUGGUCACCUGUCUGGAGCAAAUAAAAGAGCCCUGCAAUUUGAAGAUACAUGAGACAGCAGCCAAACCCCCAGUUGUUCAGCACUUCUGGUCUCUUCAGUUCUGAUAUGAUUUUAGGAUUGCUUCUUUUUUUUUUUUUGAGGCGGAGUGGAGUGCAGUGGCGCCAUCUCGUUUCAUUGCAAGUUCCGCCUCCCAUGUUCACACCAUUGUCCUGCCUCAGCCUCCCUAGUAGCUGGGACUACAGGUGCCCGCCACCACGCCCGGCUAAUUUUUUGUAUUUUAGUAGAGACGGGGUUUCACUGAGUUAGCCAGGAUGGUCUCGAUCUCCUGACCUCGUGAUCCGCCCAUUUCGGCCUCCCGAAGUGCUGGGAUUACAGGUGUGAGCCACUGCACCACGUCAGGAUUGCGUCUUAUGUUAAUGCGAAAUAUGCAUAGCUGUCAUACGAAGUAUACCACCAUUCCCUUCAGCACUCUACGUCAGAGGAGGCACGUCAGGGGAGACAAAAUUCCUCUUCGGACAGUCCCUCAAAAGACAGGAAUGUGGACAUAUAUUCCACAUUUCUCUUUGUCUCCUGAGGAAGAAGCAUAGAGUUGGGAGUUUCUCCUGGAUUGCACCAUGCUGUAUUGGGAGGAGGUCAGGCUGCGCUGGGCAUAUCUAAUAAGCUUUUUCUUCUCUUCUACAUGUUUUUGGCAUUGUGCUCAACUGAAGUAGUACAAAUUCUUAACUAUGUUCAGGAAUUCUCACAAAGGCAAUGUGAUCAGCGUGGUGUUAAGUUCAUAUAUCUAUGAAGAAACGAGGACCAGUGGUGUUUGUUUUUACGCUUUUCAUUUUAAAUUUAUAUUUUAUUUAUUAUUUUAAUUUUUGUGAGUACGUAGUACAUAUAUGUAUCUAUGGAUUAUAUCACUGAUUUUGAUGAAGGCAUGAAAUGCACAAAAAUAACAUCAGAUAAAUGGUUAUUCAUUGCCUCAACUAUUUGUUCUUUAUUUUACGAACAAUCUAAUAACAUUCUUUUAGUUACUUAAAAAUGUACAAUUAAAUUGCUUUGACUAUAGUCACUCCCGACCAGAGAAAAACCCUGUAGACAUUAGUCACUCCUCAUUCUGUCUCAAACCCUCUCCCUGACCCUCAGCCCUAGGUAGCAACUACCUAGUGCGAUCAAUCCCAUAUGCAUAGAUUACCAUAUUGUGGACAUUUCCUAUAAGCGGAAUUGCACAAUAGGGGAGCUGUUAUGACUGACAUAACACGUAGCACAAUAUUUUCAAGAUUCGUCCACAUUGUAGGCUUACCCACAGGGGGAAACCAUUUUUUUGGGGGCUUUUAGUAACACCGGUGUUUUCUCCUUCCUUACGUCCUUCUUUCCUUCCUUCCUUCCUUCCUUCCUUCCUUCCUUCCUUCCUUCCUGACUUCCUUCUUUCCUUCCCUCCUUCCUCCUAUUUCUCUCUUACUCCUUCUGCCCUCUCUCUUUCCUAUGCCUUAGGUGCAUCCCACAUUCUGCGUUUUUUUGGGGAAAUCCUCGACAGGUGCAGGAAAAUUGUGUUAUUGUAACUAUUUACCGUUAUCUCUCUUUCACGGCUCUCCAUCAGUUGUGAACAUCUAUUGGUUUAUCCCAAGUCACUAAGCAUAUUUUCAUUAGGUAAACCUGUUUUUCCUUAUACAGCUGUUUCUGGAGUAUAGGGUCGCAUACUCAUAAACCCAGUGUAACUCAGAAACGCAUCUAAUAUUCCAGUAAACCCAUCAUAACGUUGAAAAAUCGUAAAUCAAACCAUCAUAAGUCACGGUUUGUCCGUGGAUAUGGGCGUCAUCAAUUCCAUUGUAUUCAGUAAUGCUGUACACCAUUAACAAUGGCAGACUGAUUGGGAGUGGAUAUUGAUAGCAUUAUAAAAGUCAGUUAUUAGAGGGAUACUUCUUUAACCUGACUGAAGAACUGAUCUAAUGGCUUUAGUACAGUGCAUGAUUAUGUGCGAUGUUUUGAGACAGAGUAGUACAUUUGUGAAUGAAAUUUUAUGGCUUUUUUUUCACUUAGUAGGAACCAUUGUGUGUGGAAAAGUGAGAAAAUGGCUUUCUGCUGUAGGGUCUGGCAUUCAUUGUAGAUGUAAGCUUAUUUUUCUGUGAGCAAAUCUUAUUCAAUAAAAUACUACUCUUUAUACUAAAAAACAAAAACAGUGGUGAUGUGUGGUCAUUACCCUCAGCAAACUUAUCCAGGGAAAAGAAAACCAAACGCCACAACUCACUUAUAAUGGGAGCUGAAAAAUGAGAUCCCAUGGACACAGGAAGGGGAACAACACACACUGGGGCCUUCCGGGAGACAGAGCGUUAAGAAAAACAGCUACUGCAUGCUGGGCCUAAUACCUAGGUGAUGGGUUGACAGGUGCAGCAAACCACCAUGGCACACGUUUACCUUAGUAACAAAUCUGCACAUCCUGCACAUAUACCCCAGAACUUAGGAACGAAACGAAACAAAAGACAACGAAAAAGCAAUAGCAAAACGCUAAAGGCAAAAUAAAGUUUCAAACUGAGAAAGUGACAGACCAACGUCUGGUUCAAAUCAUGGUUCUCAACCCAGGUGCCAUAAGGUCAGGAUAAAGGAUGUGAUUACAUAUUGUCGAUAAGACAUGCAGCAAAUGACCAGAAUGAUUAUUCUCAACAUAUGUGUGUCUUCUAAUACAAUGGUGACGCUAACUACCGGGACAUAGCAUUAGAUUCCAAAGGGCCGAGUCCCGCCAGACAGGCCUCCCACACUAAUAACAAUGGGAAGCCCUACGUUGCUUUACCUGUGCUUCUCAGCCACUGGCUAUAAAUCAGGUUGCCACCACUCCCAGAUUUAGUUGCAUUCAUUUGCUGGAAGAGCUCACAGCACGCAGGGAAACACUUACAUUUGCCAUUGUAUUUUAGCGGACAUUGCACAAAGUUCAGAAAUAAAUGUGGGGCCCGGCAUGUGGGGAGGGGCGCACUACCUUCCAGGAAGUGUUAUCCAGAAGCUCUCUGAACCCAGUCCUUUUGGGUUAUGAUGGAGACCUCAUUCUAUAGGCAUGAUGGGUUAAACCAUAGGCUAUUGGUGAUCAAAACCACCUGGGGCUCUCCACCCUCCCUGGAAAUUGGGGUUGAGGCUUUGCCAUUCUCAGUCUGACUAAAAGAAUUUACCCAAACGGAAUUUUAAAACAGAUGAGCAUAACUGGAAUCUUAAUUAGAUGAUUGGAUUAUCUGGAGCCACACCUUGAUAUUCCUAACCCGAGCACCCUCAUCCAACGAAUGCUCCACCCAACUGGCUCCCAAGUCUCUACGUGGUCCCAGAGCAAAAGGAUGUUGAUACAACGCAUAUCUCCACCUUUUCUUCAAAGUCUUUUCGCUUACACGGAAAGACUUCUUCAACUGCCAUGCAUCAGGGUCAGGGGGAGGUCUUGUUACAACACAGAUCUGCGGAUCUCCGGCGUUUGACUGUGGCAAGGAUGCUGCUGGUGUCAAAACCACAACGUGGGAACCACAGAACCACUAGUGGGUUUUCAGUGUUUCAGUGCAUACAAUUCCUAAUAUUUCUGGCCAAGAAAACUUGUAAGUUCUUAGAUUGUCCCAAAGGUGGCGCAUGAAAUCAAAGCAGGAGAACAGUUUCCUACGAGGUGUAGCCUGGGAAAGUUGGGGGUGACUGAUGGAAAGGAGGAGUGAAGCUCCGCCCUUUCCGCUGCUAGGCUGCGCCCGAGGCUAUUUAAACCCACCCUGGCUGGCCUGUACUCAGAUCUUCGCGGAGCGGAUCAGCGGCCGGAGCGUUUGGCGGACUCUGCGUGGACUUGGAGCUCACAGCGUCUUGCGACUUGGAAGCGGAUUCAGAGGACAGGACAGAACACUUGGGCAAGUGAAUCUCUGUCUGUCUGUCUGUCUGUCUGUCUGUCUCAUUGGUUGGUUGAUUUCCAUUUUCUUAAGGGGCACAUACCUCACACCGCACACACACAAACACACACACGCGCACACACACACACACGCACACACACGCACACACACUCCUUCCUUCUGCGAGUUAGUACAUUAGUAGGGGCCCCUGGGAGCUGCAGGUUUCCUAAUCAUGUCUGCACCUAAGAACAGUAGGGUCUUGUGUGGCUCUUCUUAUGAACGGUCCCCCAGCCCGAACUCGCCAAGGUCCAUGCGAGCCUCACCCAGCUUCUCCCUCUCCCCUCUCAGAAACUCAGGCUUAAGGGGAAGCUCCUCACCAGGGAUCCGGAGCUACCAUUCACCAUCCCCUAGGGCUUCACCACACUCACCUCUGUCAUCACCAGAAUCCCACAAGCUCCCAUUUCCCUGUCCUCACCGUGAUGGGCAAUCAAUGAAGCCAUUGGGCUCUCCCGUGUCCUCCUCUGAGGAUUCCUCAGAGUCCCCACGUUCAUCAAUAAUAUACCACAUGUUCUUACUGCCAUCACCCAGCAGCUCACCCCCAGCUCUCGGGGGGUCUCCUGUGUCUCCCAGCUACUCUCCAAACAACGCCAGAUUUCAGCUGGAGUCAGCCCCCCACACCCAGGAAUCACCUACAAACUCACGAGCCUCACGGUGCUCCACCCCCGUGUCUUUCAUCUCUUCACCCCCAGGCCUCAGGGACUCUCCUGUGGCUCCCAGUUACUCUCCAGCCAUCCCCAGGUUCCUGCGGGAGUCAGCCCCAUGCACCCAGGAGUCCCCCAGAGACUCACAGGUCUCGGGAGAAAGUGAGCGGUCCCCCAGCCCUGACUCCUCAAGAUUCAUGCCUGCCUCACCCAGCUUCUCCCUCUCCCCUCCCAGAAACUCAGACCCAAGGGGCAGCUCCUCACCAGGGAUGUGGAAGUCCUCUACAUCAUCCCGCAGGGCUUCAGCACUCUCACAUCCGUCAUCAACAGAAUUCCACAACUUUACGUUUCCCUUUCCUAACCAAGCAGGACAGUCACUCAUGUCAUUGUGUUCUCCCGUGACCUCCUCUGGAGAUUCUUCACAGUCACCUCAUUCAUCAAUAAUAUACCAUAUGUUCUUACUGCCAUCAUCCAGCAGCUCACCCCCAGCCACCCAUGACUCUCCUGUCUGUCCCAGCUACUCUCCAACUACGCCCAGAUUUCAGCGGGAGUCUGUACCCCACACCCCAGAAACACCUACAAACUCACAGACCUCAGUGAGAUCCUCGCCAGUCUCUCUCACGUCUUCACCCCCAGCCCUUACGGACCCUCCAGUCUGUCCCAGCUACUCUCCAACCACGCCCACAUUUCAGCGCGGGUCAGUUCCAGGAUCGAAGGGAUCACCACCAAGCCCACCGCUUUCACUGAGUUACUCCCCAGUCUCUAGCACGUCUUUAUCUCCAACCCUCAGGGACUCGCCUGUCUGUCCCAGCCACUCUCCAAACACGCCCACACUUCAGCGGGAGUCCGUUGCAGGCACCCAGAAGUCACCACCAAACUCACCAAUUUCACUGCGUUACUCCCCAGUCUCUCUCAUGUCUUCACCAUCCCUCAGGGACUCUCCCGUCUGUCCCAGCUACUCUCCAACCACGCCCACAUUUCAGCUGGAGUCAGUUCCAGGCACCCCGGAAUCACCACCAAACUCACCAAUUUCACUCAGUUACUCCUCAGUCUCUAGCACGUCUUUAUCUCCAACCCUCAGGGACUCUCCUGUGUGUCCCAGCUACUCUCCAACCACGCCCACACUUCAGCGGGAGUCAGUUCCAGGCACCCAGGAAUCACCACCAAACUCACCAAUUUCACUCAAUUACUCUCCAGUCUCUCUCGUGUCUUCACCAGCCCUCAGGGACUCUCCUGUCUGUCCCAGUUACUCUCCAACCACGCCCACAUUUCAGCUGGAGUCAGUUCCAGGCACCCCGGAGUCACCACCAAACUCACCAGUUUCACUCAGUUACUCCCCGGUCUCUCUCAUGUCUUCACCCCCAGCCCUCAGGGACUCUCCUGUGUGUCCCAGCUACUCUCCAACCAUGCCCAGAUUUCAGCGGGAGUCUGUUCCAGGCACCCAUGUAUCACCACCAAACUCAGCAGUUUCACUGAGUUACUCCCCAGUCUCUCUCAUGUCUUCACCCCCAGACCCCUGGGACUCUCCUGUCUGUCCCAGCUACUCUCCCACCACGCCCAGAUUUCAGCGGGAGUCAGCCUCCCACACUCCAGAAUCAGAUACAGACUCACAGACUUCACUGAGCUCCUCCCUGGUCUCUCUCAGGUCUUUGCCCUCAUCCCACAGGGACUCUUGUGUCUCUUUCAGCUACUCUCAAAACUUCUCUAGAUUCCAGCUGGAGUCAGUUCCAGGCACCCACGAUACACCACCGAACUCACGAAUUUCACUGACUUACUCCCCAGUCUCCCUCAUGUUCUCACCCCCAGCCCUCAGGGACUCUUCUGUCUCUCUCAGCUACUCUCCAACCAUCUCCAGAUUUCACCUGGAGUCAGCUUCCCACACCCUGGAAUCACCUGCAAACUCACGGACCUUACUGCAACCAUCCCCCAUUUCUUUCAACUCUUCACCCCCUGCCUUCAGGGACUCUCCUGGGUCUCCCAGCUUCUCUCCAGCCUUCCCCAGAUUUCUGCCACAGUCAGCCCCAGGCACCCAGGACAACCCUAGACACUCACAGGCCUCACCAGACUAUCUCCCUAUGACCUGUACCUAUACAGGGAUGGCUCCCACGCAUCCCUCAGUGACCCCAAACCCAUCUCCACUUACACUCAGGCACUCCCAGGGCCUGACAGCUACUCCCCGUUAUUGUCCUUCAGUUCGAAGCCCUGGCCAAUCUAUUAGCCCACAUGACGCAGUUACCUGGCCAUUUCUCCACGGUUCCCGGGAGGGCCCCACACCCAGCCGCACAAGAGCCCCUCCUGCAUUCCGUCCUCACACGCAGGCCUGUCCAUCUACUUGCUACUGUCACACUCUUGCCAGCAGAAGAGGCCCCUGUAAUGGCCGAUAUCACCACCCAGUCUAUCCUCACCCCACAGCUGUGCAGCGGGAACCCCCUGCUGGCCCACGUGGCUGCCACAGCCCAUGCUGGCACGACGCUCCAGCAGGUCGGCGUUCCUGCGGGCCAAACUACCGGUGACGUGUCUAGCGUGACCCUCCUUCCUGGCAGUGACACUGUUGAUGUGAACCCCAAUUUCACAUCUGUCGUUUGUAAAUAGGACCAUUUUCCCUUUUCGCUCUCCCUUCCAUUCACAGGGCUUUUCAUUCUCUCUGUUACUGCCUCCGUUUCAGAUAUUUACUCACCUUUUUCUCUCUCACUUUGUCUGCCAUGGGCUCUAUGAGAGUGCGCCACAUAAGAUUCCCCAAUUAAAAGUCGUGAAUUGAGUGGCUUUUAGUAUACCUGUGGUUGUGCACAUUCAAAUUUAAUUCGCAAUUCAUUGUAGAACGUCUUAUCACUCCCGGCCAGAGAAAAACCCUGUAGACAUUAGUCACUCCUCAUUCUGUCUCAAACCCUCUCCCUGACCCUCAGCCCUAGGUAGCAACUACCUAGUGCGAUCAAUCCCAUAUGCAUAGAUUACCAUAUUGUGGACAUUUCCUAUAAGCGGAAUUGCACAAUAGGUGAGCUGUUAUGACUGACAUAACACGUAGCACAAUAUUUUCAAGAUUCGUCCACAUUGUAGGCUUACCCACAGGGGGAAACCAUUUUUUUGGGGGCUUUUAGUAACACCGGUGUUUUCUCCUUCCUUACGUCCUUCUUUCCUUCCUUCCUUCCUUCCUUCCUUCCUGACUUCCUUCUUUCCUUCCCUCCUUCCUCCUAUUUCUCUCUUACUCCUUCUGCCCUCUCUCUUUCCUAUGCCUUAGGUGCAUCCCACAUUCUGCGUUUCUUUGGGGAAAUCCUCGACAGGUGCAGGAAAAUUGUGUUAUUGUAACUAUUUACCGUUAUCUCUCUUUCACGGCUCUCCAUCAGUUGUGAACAUCUAUUGGUUUAUCCCAAGUCACUAAGCAUAUUUUCAUUAGGUAAACCUGUUUUUCCUUAUACAGCUGUUUCUGGAGUAUAGGGUCGCAUACUCAUAAACCCAGUGUAACUCAGAAACGCAUCUAAUAUUCCAGUAAACCCAUCAUAACGUUGAAAAAUCGUAAAUCAAACCAUCAUAAGUCACGGUUUGUCCGUGGAUAUGGGCGUCAUCAAUUCCAUUGUAUUCAGUAAUGCUGUACACCAUUAACAAUGGCAGACUGAUUGGGAGUGGAUAUUGAUAGCAUUAUAAAAGUCAGUUAUUAGAGGGAUACUUCUUUAACCUGACUGAAGAACUGAUCUAAUGGCUUUAGUACAGUGCAUGAUUAUGUGCGAUGUUUUGAGACAGAGUAGUACAUUUGUGAAUGAAAUUUUAUGGCUUUUUUUUCACUUAGUAGGAACCAUUGUGUGUGGAAAAGUGAGAAAAUGGCUUUCUGCUGUAGGGUCUGGCAUUCAUUGUAGAUGUAAGCUUAUUUUUCUGUGAGCAAAUCUUAUUCAAUAAAAUACUACUCUUUAUACUAAAAAACAAAAA